CUCCCUGCACGGCCUCCCGUGCGCCCCUGUCAGACUGUGGCGGCCGGUCGCGCGGUGCGCUCUCCCUCCCUGCCCGCAGCCUGGAGAGGCGCUUCGUGCUGCACACCCCCGCGUUCCUGCCGGCACCGCGCCUGCCCUCUGCCGCGCUCCGCCCUGCCGCCGACCGCACGCCCGCCGCGGGACAUGGCACACGCACCGGCACGCUGCCCCAGCGCCCGGGGCUCCGGGGACGGCGAGAUGGGCAAGCCCAGGAACGUGGCGCUCAUCACCGGUAUCACAGGCCAGGAUGGUUCCUACCUGGCUGAGUUCCUGCUGGAGAAAGGCUAUGAGGUCCAUGGAAUUGUACGGCGGUCCAGUUCAUUUAAUACGGGUCGAAUUGAGCAUCUGUAUAAGAAUCCCCAGGCUCACAUUGAAGGAAACAUGAAGUUGCACUAUGGCGAUCUCACUGACAGUACCUGCCUUGUGAAGAUCAUUAAUGAAGUAAAGCCCACAGAGAUCUACAACCUUGGAGCCCAGAGCCACGUCAAAAUUUCCUUUGACCUCGCUGAGUACACUGCGGACGUUGACGGAGUUGGCACUCUACGACUUCUAGAUGCAGUUAAGACUUGUGGCCUUAUCAACUCUGUGAAGUUCUACCAAGCCUCAACAAGUGAACUUUAUGGGAAAGUGCAGGAAAUACCCCAGAAGGAGACCACCCCUUUCUAUCCCCGGUCACCCUAUGGGGCAGCAAAACUCUAUGCCUAUUGGAUUGUGGUGAACUUCCGUGAGGCGUAUAAUCUCUUUGCAGUGAACGGCAUUCUCUUCAAUCAUGAGAGUCCCAGAAGAGGAGCUAAUUUCGUUACUCGAAAAAUUAGCCGGUCAGUAGCUAAGAUUUACCUUGGACAACUGGAAUGUUUCAGUUUGGGAAAUCUGGAUGCCAAACGAGAUUGGGGCCAUGCCAAGGACUAUGUGGAGGCUAUGUGGUUGAUGUUGCAGAAUGAUGAGCCGGAGGACUUCGUUAUAGCUACUGGGGAGGUCCAUAGUGUCCGGGAAUUUGUCGAGAAAUCAUUCUUGCACAUUGGAAAAACCAUUGUGUGGGAAGGAAAGAAUGAAAAUGAAGUGGGCAGAUGUAAAGAGACCGGCAAAGUUCACGUGACUGUGGAUCUCAAGUACUACCGGCCAACUGAAGUGAUCUUCAUGCAGAAAAAGUUACUUGUUCCUUAGUACUGCCAGCUGUGUGCUUCUUGACCCAGGGGUAGAAAGGAUGAUCGUGGUGGAAGGUAGGGAUAUGCUGAAUUGGUGAUCGACUUCUGAUUCUGCCUAAACGGUAUGUUUCAAGGGAGUGUGACAGGCGCUGAGAUCCAGCAAGCUCUACAGCUCCUCCUAGAACUGCAGUAUCCCCAGUAGGCUAGAGAGCAGCCACCAAGGAAGACAUCAGGCUAUCAUCUGCUUUUAUCUGCCAACCACCCCCCAUGCUCCUCCCUUGGAAACCUGUCUGCAAAAACCCAUCUUUGUACUUGCUCCCUAGAGCCAGCUGAGUGUCACUUUGAUAGUCUAAAAUCUAUGUUGGUUUACUAUUGCUGAUGUAACAAGUAAUCACAAACUUAGUGGCUUAAAACUACCCAGAUUCAUUGUCUUACAGUUCUGGAGGUCAGAAGACCAAAUGGAGUCCCACUGAGCUAAAUCAAGGUGCUGGCAAAGCCACCUUCCUUGUUGAGGCUCCAGAGUUCUUGGACAGUGAGAUUUUCUCUUGGCAGGGAAUACUGAGUUAAUCACUUGGAACCGGUGCUGGGCUAGUGUUUUCCAUGGAAUGGAUAGCAUGUUGUUAAUCACUUUGCGGACUAAACCAAAAUGGAAGACGCUGGUGCAUCAUCUAUUUAAAAUUGCAUAAUGUACACACUCAGAAAACACCGCUGAUACAUUUGGGCAACUGGAAAUGAGGACAGGUCGUACUUGAGCCUGAGGGACAAGGACAGGCUUCCUAAUAAAGGGGAGUUUUAGAGCAGGGCUUUGGAAAGAUUUGUAAUUAAAAGAGAGAGUUGGGGGACGGGGUGUAAGAACUGGGAAAGAAUUCACAAUUGGGGCAGGAGGUGCUGUGGGAAUGAACCAGCCGCAUGAACAGAGACAUAGGCAGGGACUCUGUCAGGUGGAGUGGGUGGGUGGCCCAGUCUGGGAACCCUGAGAAGCAAGGCUGGUAGAGCCAAUAUCACCACACCCUGCCCUGGCCAGGCCUUCUCUCACGCAGCCAGCAGGCCACCCCUCUUCACCGCCUCACCUCCAAGCCUGUCUGUGCAGCAGCUUAGCCACUCCUCUUAUUUGUACCUCCUAUUUUCUUGCCUUUUUCUUUCUUGCUGUCACGAGUCUUAAAACCAGUCAUAUGUCAUCAUUAAACUCCACAUGGCCACUAUUCUGAUACCAUUAAUCUGUCUUUUGAUACCUGCCAUCUGACCCCUGAUGGGUUCAAAUUCUGGAAGAGUGUCUCCUCACCUGUUCCAUUAAGUUAGUUAAACAAGUUUUGUGUUUGAGACAAAUUCUUAAACAGUUCCCAGCUGUUUCAGUGAUUAAAAGGCAGAGCCAGGAAUAGGGAAGGCCUUACUUUCAUGAGAGAGAUUUGUUUAUAGCAUAAACGUGGAUCCUUAACAGUAACUCAGAGAAAACCAAUCUAAAGAUGUUUUUAAUCUUUUUUUACAUAUUCUUCGACUUCAUAAUGAAAUGUUUCCCUAUUUUCCAGGGAUUUUGUUGAGAAUGAAAUUAAUUCUGUGUGAAUGUUUUUCACAGUGGUAUUAGAAAGACACUGUAUAUUUUAAAUUCAGGCUGUUUCUAUUAUUUUUUGAAAAGAGGUCAGUGGAGAAAAAUGUGCCUAACAUCGUCAUCUAAAACCUGCUGUUUGAAUUUUGGGGAAUUUGUCAUUUUUUCUAAGGCAAGUUACUAAGGUAUUGAAGUUAAUAAGACGUAUUUGUUUCUGAAUCAGUUUUUGUUGUGGAGGAUUAGAAAGUACUAUAGUCCCUUAUUGAAAUUCUAAAAUUUAAAAAGUAUAGUGGUAGUUUGAAUAUGUCCUACUAGCUUGCAUUAUAAGUUUUAAAGUAUGUAUCUCAACACCUUUUAUUCCCAGCUCUCAAACUUUUGAAGUCUUCUAGAAGCUCCUAACCUCUCCUUACUUCUGUUUUUCCUGCUACAACAUAACGAUGAGUAUUUUCCCACUGAUCUCAAUAGGCAUGUUGAAAAAACUGAUGCAAUAUUAGUUACAAGACCCUGCACAAGUGUCAGCUCCUUGGUGCAGCCUGCACCUGUUCCCCCAGGCAGUCAGCACUUACCGCUUAUCCCAUUGCAUUGUGAUGGGUCAUUUCCACCUGGGGUCCUGGGGGAAGAAUGACAUCGGAGGGCCUUGAAGACGACCUGGCACAUUGUCAGGGGAUAAAGAAUGAAUGAAUGUGCACAUUGCCAAAGAAUCAUUCUUAUGCUUUACAGCCAGCUCUGAUAGAACCAAAAUUAUUCAAACCAGUGUAUUAAACUAUUAGAGAGCAAUAGUCUAAACUAUACUAAAUAGCAAAGGGAAUAAAAAUAAUAAUGUUCCUCUUUCUAUUUGAGAUUCCAUGGCAAGAUGAGUGUUAAGUUCACUCACAACUUACACUUGUAUAUCCAACCUUUGAAAAGGUCAUAUUUCGUUUCUAUUGCUUUACCUCUAUACAUGUCUUUUCACUAAUUCUUUCAUUUCUGCCACUUUCCUGUCUCCUUAUGUUUCUGCUGAUGUUCUCUCCUUUUUUCUUCAUCUGUUCUGAAACUCUUAUUUUCAUAGGUUCUGUUCGUUUCUCCACUUCCCUCUGCACCUUUCUUGUUGAUCUAUCCCAACUGUCUCACACAAGCUCAGCACUCCAGAUGUGCUCCCUGGCUCCUCUCCACAGGAAGACCUGGUGAUGCCAUAUUACAGCCACUGCAGCCCGGCUCCACCCUUAGACCACUAGGGCAUGAUGCCUCCGGCAUCCACAGCAUAUGCACAUUGUGGGAAAAUCUCAUAGUAUCUUGAAGUCUUGGCAGACAGCAUCAACAAUAAUGCAUAUGCAAAAGGCAUCCAAGGUUGCUUCUGUCUGAAGAGAGUACGACUGCCAACUGGAGGCAUUGCCGGCUCUGAGCCUCCAUAAGAAAUGCCCCAUUGUCAGCCACCAUCUUUCCUUUACCCACUCUGAGGCUAUAUUUGUGGAACAAAGUGUCACCUAGCAUAAAAGACACUCAGUUCUCUGGCUUUCCCCAUGACACGCGUUUCUCUGCUACUCUGAAACUUUCUGAAUUACAAAGUGAGAAAUAAGUUCUACUCAGUGAAUGGCCAUCAUGGCUGGUAUUGGUAUCGUGGAACCAAGGUCUUCCGGAAACCUGGUGGCAUGAUAUUCCUUUUUCUCUUCACCUAGAAUCUUCAAUGUUUUUCUUUUUUUUUUUUAAUGUAAGUGCAAAGAACUUAAAUAUAUGAUUGUGUAAGAUGAUAGUCAUUUAGAACAACAUUUUUUAAAUUUCUGAAAAAGUGAGGCCGGGCACAGUGGCUCACGCCUGUAAUCCCAGCACUUUAGGAGGCCAAGGCAGGUGGAUCACGAGGUCAGGAGAUCGAGACCAUCCUGACUAACAAAGUGAAAUCCCGUCUGUACUAAAAAUACAAAAAAAUUAGCUGGGCGUGGUGGUGGGCGCCUGUAGUCCCAGCUACUUGGGAGGCUGAGGCGGGAGAAUGGCGUGAAUCCAGGAGGCGGAGCUUGCAGUGAGCCAAGAUCAUGCCACUGCACUCCAGCCUGGGCGACAGAGUGAGACUCCCUCUCAAAAAAAGUCUGAAAAAGUGUUGGGCUUAUAGAGAUUUUCCUAAUAAGGUGUACAGUGUCUUCUUCUUUGCACAUCCAUUUUGGUGGAAAAUUCAGUCAAAUGCACUAGAAUAGUCUUUGGAUAUGUUUUCUAAAACAAGUAUCUAAUUCCCACAUGAAGAGAAAUGGCCUGAUUGAGUAUGCCUGUCUUACCAAAACUGUUAACUUACAGUGAGGAUGUGAAAAAAUAAGAACUCAGAUAGGCCCGUGGAUCAGAUGAAUAAGAAAAAGAGAAGAGACUAUGGAUAAAAACAGUUGCUGAUUUUCCUUUGAGAUGUUUGUGCUUCAUGCCGCCAAAUUGAGAUGAGAGAAAAGCCAAUUUCAUGCAGUUUGGCACAACUGUAAAAUGCAGCACAAACACACGUACGUGUAUGUGUGUGUGUGUGUGUGUCCCAUUGAUCCAAAAAGCCUGUUUGUCUAUUGGCAAGACGAAAUAUUAUCUUCAUGCAUCACCACCUCCUCCUAAAGGUAGGAUGGGGAUGGCCGUCAGUGCCAAUACAUUGUCUCUUCUUUCAGCUGGCGGGGGUGGGCAGUGGGAGGGAGCCACGGGGCGGAGACGCAGAGCAAACAGUGCCAGCACUGGAUCCCGGCGUGGGCCGGUGGUGGGUGCCAGGAGCAGCCAGGGCCUGUGCCUAGUCGUCACAUGUGGUGCUGAGCAACCACCAACUCUUCCCAGGAAGGAGGUGAAAAGAUAACACACACUGGAGUCCAGUGGAGGCGAGGACACUUCAUCCCACAGGGACCGCAGUGGCCAAGGGAAUGGUUUUAAUGGUGGUUUGACUUGGCAUACUUAUGAAAAGGCUAGCGCCCACCCGCUGGCCUGUGGGUUUAUUUGGCAAAACAUAAAACAGAGUCAGUUGCUUGUCCUUGAGAGUGGCCACUAUGGAUCUACCACAUUUCUGACUUGUCAGUCUGACAUCCGUGGCUGGAUUCUACAUAGUCUUGUGUUGAUGGAUUUGUUGCUUUGGGAGAAACGCAGAUAUGAUGGCAUGGCCUUCUCACUAUCUGCAGCAGAAACGGCCUUGUGUCUGCCCCGUGUCCCUGGUCAUCCACGGACAUUGGUCAGGCUUUCUGAUUCACACCACUUUCUCCUCAGCCCUCCAACUAAGUAAUAUUUAUAUUGUUCUGCUAACAACCUCUAUUGAAAUCCAAACUUAAUAACCUAUUGCUUGCUAGAAAUAUUCUCCUCUUCCUUUCUGCCUGUUUCAUGAUCUUGGUUUUUUUUUUAAAGAAUUCAACCCUUUUGCUUUUUCCCUUUCUCCAUCUUUAUAACUUUUUCAGACAAUUGAACUUCUGUCUGAACUUCUGAGCUUUCCGAUACCCUCAUACUUUGUGGUCAGCAUCAGAGACAUCAAAGUAAAGUGGGUAUUUGUUUCAAACCCUGAGUUGAUGAUAAGCCAUUAUGUCUGCUGCGUCUUCUCUCCAUGUGAGUGACAUUUUGCACCCCAGGCUUAGUUAUAGGGAGCAAGUUAGGAAUGUGUGUUUUGCAGUUUCUGUUGUUUAUGUAAACCAUCGAUAUCAGUUUAUUCAUCUGAAGGAAAUAAGAAAAAACACUUCAGUCAAAAUAAUUAGGAGCUAAGAUAAGAACACAGCACUUCAAAGUUCAUUUAGCUACUUACAUCUUCUACUUUACACGUCAUCUCAGCUUCCCUAUCUCCUAAGUGAAGGAUGAUUAUGAUAAACUUCACAAAAGUAGUGGGAGGUUAAAUUAGUGUUUGUGAAGCAUGUUGAGAUCUUAUGAUCAAAGAUACCGGAGUAUUGCAGAAUAGUGUGAUUACUAUCAAAGAAAAGAAUUCCUCAAACCAAGAGUCUGGAUUAAUCUGACUUAAUUUUCCAGCAUCUUCUGUAUCUGACUGAAUUUUCCAGCAUCUUCUAUACCUUCUAUAUCUGAAGCCCCAAACCUCCAAUCUCUUGCAGUUUUCUCGUGAUCUUAGAGUCCGUUUCUAAGCAUUGAAGAGGGUUAGAGAGUAGGCUGCAGUCAUAAACUUGUAAACAGAGGAGAAGUGUUGGGUGUUAAUGAAGGCUCAGGCGAGGGGCCGGAUGGGGCUUUGGGGGGCAUGUUCGGCUGGUGACUGUGCAGUGCUGCUCUCAGCAGCCACCGUUUGGCUGGUGCUCGGGUGGGGCCUUCACUAUGCCAGAAAAACUGUCCCUCCACCCAGCUCAUUCCUUAGAAUCAACAGGGACUUUCAUCCAUGCUGCACAAAAUCGGACGGAAAAGAUGGCUUUCCACAAGUUUCCCAAGUCACUUAAGGGGCACGGAAGGGGUAUGCAGGCAGCCGGGGUGUCAGAGGCAAAGACAGGCUGAUAGCACAGAGAUAAGCAAGGUGGAUGGAAAACCAUACCUAGACAUAACGUGUGCAAAAAUUGCAGAGUAGUAUCUCCAAAAUCACAGGCCACAAAUACACAGAUUUGGUGCAAACUGGCAAAAUGAGUUUGUACAUUUAUUUCCCACCCAUGUGUUUCAUUUUGCCUGUAAUCAUCAGAGCUGUUGUGGAUGGGUGGGUUACCCAAGUGUUCUUAAAGAGGCAACCCAUUUCUUCUCAGGCAAUACUACUACUUUAAGCAAAACCGCAGGCAUCCUUUGUCAAGGGUGGCUACCCUAGUCCAUGGUUCUUAAGCCUAGUACGUCAGACUCAUCCAGAAAGCUGUUGAAAAUACAGUCUUCCAGGAUUCAUCCUCAAACCACUUGAGCGGUGGACCCUGGAAACGUAGGACUCUGCAGGGAUCCUGAGGCAGCCGGCUCUGAGGCUGGCCAAGCCUCGGUAAGUGGGGGCAGCUGUGCCCUGGGCUGCAGUCAGGGAAUGAUGCACACAGUUGGGUUGUCCCUAACCUUGUUGGUUUCAUUCACCUCUUGAAGAAUUAGAUAAAAGCUGAUUCCCCCCAGGGGAAAAUGCUCAGAAUACAUCAUGUAUGUAGUUGUAGGGAAUUGUGCCUGUCCAGCUGUCCAUGCGGAGAAAACAAAGCUGAACUGCCAGGUCCGGCUCCUUUCUUCUCCAGCCCCAAGUUUUUGCUUGGCUUGGCACAUCCUUUCAUAGGUGUACGUAUUUUGUAAAUGUUCAUGUCCAGUGAUUAAAACUGUCAUUGGUAUAAUUUCUGACGAUAUGUAGUCAACCCCUUCACAAGUCUGUCGUUAAGCCCUCCACAAACUCACAGGGGUGCUUUGGAAGAGCUUGACAUCCGCCCUCCCCAAUGGAACAUAAGAGCCAUUCACACCCCCGCCCUGCAAGGGAGGGUGUGCUUAGGACCUGGACAUUGAGCUUGGCAGUAUCACCAGAUCAUUUACCGAUUGAAGUUAAAUUGAUGAUAGAAAUGUAGACGUCAAGAUUUUUGUGCCUAGGUAGUCUCAGCUUCCCUGACCCCAUCCUCGGAGAGCUCCAGGUCUAGGGGGACCAUUCCCAAGGGGAACCUCAAAAGUGUAUCUGCCAUGUCAGGGCAGACGUGUGUUUUGGUUGUUUUUGGUGAAGCCCCAGAGGGCAUUGUCCCUACACAGUUCUCUGAUAGGCGGAAGCUCCAUCAGGUCUGACCACAGCCUGGUUAUACCACGGCAGGUCCAGAGCAGGUGGCUGCUCAGGGUUUAGGGACUGAAUGAAUGCCGCAGACGUGGAAAAGAAAAUCAACUAGCUGUUUUAGGCAUCUGAUCAAUCAGUGUGAUUGGUUUCUUUACCAAGUUGAUGAGUAGAUCUGCUGUGUUCUCAGCAGUAAUGUGGUUAAGCUUCUCAGGAAUAUACACAUACACAAAUGUUUUCCCCGGUCUGGUGGAGGGUAGUAAUAAAAAGCAGAGCAUUUAGAGACAAAGUCAACUUGACAGGCAGAGUGGAGGUAAACAGUCUUCCUCUGCAGGAGCAGUGUUGACAAGCAGUGAUUCUUGGGAAGCGUACAGCUGUAGCACGGGCUCUGACUUCAGGGACUUCAGCAGUAUAAAAACAAUUUUUAAAUACCCAAAGUCAUUUAUUUUAAGUGUACUUGUAUGGUUUGGGGUUUUAUGUUAUCGGUUUAUAUAUAUGUGUGAUUUUUAUUAACUAUUUCCAGAAAUAAUUCUGCAGUUAAGCCAAAAGCUGCUGCAUGAAGCAAAAACUCUUCCUCCAUAGAUACCCUGCCUCAGUCGAGUUAGGCAGGUUUAGCCCAACCAAAGGACUGUAUUUGUUGAGAGAAGAGACAUUUGUUUUCUCCCCAAACUUCAAGCUCUGGUUUUGAAACAUAACUCUCAGUCCCAUCUCUAAAUCCUAGUUACAGCAUUAAUUCUCAAUAAGUUCUUCUUUUUGCACGUACUCUCAUGUAAGCAGCAGUCUAAAUAGCCAUGUAAGGGCAGCCAGAGGAGUGGGUUUGUGCCUUGGGGAACAGAGGAGCCAAGGCCCACCCACGUUACUUGUCCACUUCUCCUUCCAUCUGUGACAAUCAGCUCCAAGCAUUAAGGGCUUCUCCUGGUCCUGGGGGCCAGGCAACACGUCACCUCUGAGAUGUUGGCCUUUGCCACCGUGGCUUCUCCAGCACAGAGCCUCAUUGUCACUUCCUCCAGCUGCUCAGGGAACAUGAUCUUCACUGUUGUCAUGUCAGAUGAGGAAAUUGGGCCACCAGGAAGCCGAGUGACUUGCCCAAGGUCACGCUGUGUGCUAGUGGCACAGCCAGUUUCCAGGCCGUGCUCCCCCACGAAGCCUCUGCAACUUUCCUCCCAGAUCACGUGCACUGGGUCACCCAAAAACUUUGCCCUUCUGCACAUUAGCCUCUAAGGACAGCUGCUCUAAGCACUUUCUAGCCAGGCCCCUCAGCAGCAGCACUACAAGGGUGGCUGGCACUCUGGUUCUGUAGACACUGUCUCCUGCCUUUUCUCAGUGCUGCAGUGGGUGUAUCUGCACCUACUUAAUGGUCUGAAUCUAUAAACCAGCAGUCAGACACCUGCUGUGCAUUCAGGGGACAUAACCUGUCAUGCCUACCUGUGGAGCUGAGUCAGUGUACACGGUUCUCGGCAAUCAGGGGACAUCAGACAGCUGCACCCUCUUUUCCAGUGACACAGGCACCAGGUAUGAAGGCUUUGAGGGAUUUUCUGGAAGUAGGAAGGGUCAGGGCCCAACUGAACAUGUCACCACAGCACCUGACAAUGGCUUUUUGUCCUUUUAGUGUAUGACUGGACACACUUACUUACCAUGUAAAGGUGCUUCUUUUUUACAUUUAAAACCCAAAGCUGUGAGAUGCAGCGUACAGAGACGUGACCCCGGUUGGCCUUUUGCUGUUUCAGAUGGCAGUACUCAGAGGAACGCCAGCCAGGCCCAGAGGCCCCCGGCGCUCACUGGCCUUUCUUUCAUGUGCCCUUGGAGUUCUUAGAAUAGACUAUGAGAUUUUAAUUCAAAAGGAAUAUUCUACCAGCAGUUUAUAAUAGGCAUGGUUUGAGGAAAACCCAAACCUGCUUUUCCCAAGAUCUAAACCAUUUGAUGCACCAGUUAUCUGAUGCAGUGGGGCUCUCGCCCGAUCCAUUCUUUGGAGCUACACCAUACUCGAUUGUGCGGUGACUGACUUAGCCCCGGGCAGUUCAGACUUGGACCCACCGUGUGGCAUGUUUGUCCUCGUUGCUGUUGCUGUAUUGACAACGCCUUCAGAGGUGGUUUCGAGUGCAAGCCCCCUACCCGCCUUCCCUCCACUCCUCAUCUGCCCUCCAGCUUCUCCAAACACGCUUCGCUGCCUGCUGGGAAUGCUGCCUUGCAAAGGAGUGACGUCUCAAGUGUCGGGAAAGUUACAGCCUUCGAGUUGUUUCCUUCCCUACCUUUGAGAUAUACCCAGAUGCCGCAUUUUGUUUCACGCUUUUCUGUGGAUGGUGAGCAAAUGGCUGAUUCUUUAUGGCCCUCAGAGCCCCAGGAGGGUGUGGACAAGCACCUUUCCCACUUGAUACUUCUGGAUAUUUCCUUUCUAUGCCAUUAAAAUCGGAUGAGUGCUGUA